GGGGCAGCCCUGGCCAGCCCAGGAGAACCCGCGAGCCCAGCGGCGCCUGCACCUGCGGCUUCCGGGAGCCGGGCGGCUUUGCGAGGCUCACUAGGUCUGAGAGGUCGGAGGCCGCCAGUGUCGCUGCUGAAGGGUGGACCAGGCGGGAUCGCGGAUUCUGGGCUAGAUCGCAGACUUGAAUUCGACACCAAAUUUUGGAACUUAAAAAGAAGAUUCUUAAAACUUACAAUCCAGAUUCUGGGAGUUCUGAUGAAUAUGCAGUCAGCCCAGGGCUUCCCAGCUGUCUUCAUCCAGGCCUGCGCCGGUGUUCACAGUGGUCCUCAUCUAAGCCAGCCAAGAAGAUCUCUGUCAUCCACGUGACAGCCAGCCCAGAUGUCCCUAGCCGUCCUCAUCAAGGCCAGCCAGUUUGCUUACACGUGUGCUAAUUGGAGCCAGCCACCCUCAUAGAGGCCAUCCCAGAUUACGAUGAGGACCUGGUGCAGGAAGCUUCAUCUGAAGAUGUCCUGGGCGUUCAUAUGGUGGACAAAGACACAGAGAGAGACAUUGAGAUGAAACGGCAACUACGGCGACUACGGGAGCUCCACCUAUACAGCACAUGGAAGAAGUACCAAGAGGCGAUGAAGACAUCCUUGGGAGUUCCACAAUGUGAGCGUGACGAAGGCUCCUUGGGCAAGCCAUUGUGUCCACCCGAGAUACUCUCGGAGACGUUGCCAGGCUCUGUGAAGAAAAGGGUAUGCUUUCCAUCAGAAGAUCAUCUAGAGGAGUUUAUAGCAGAACAUCUCCCUGAAGCAUCCAAUCAGAGUCUCCUCACUGUUGCCCAUGCAGACGCAGGCACCCAAACCAACGGUGACCUGGAAGACCUGGAGGAGCAUGGGCCAGGGCAGACAGUCUCUGAGGAAGCCACAGAAGUUCACACGAUGGAGGGGGACCCAGACACACUGGCCGAAUUUCUGAUCAGGGAUGUACUUCAGGAGCUGUCCAGUUACAACGGUGAGGAGGAGGACCCAGAGGAGGUGAAGACAUCCUUGGGAGUUCCACAACGUGGUGACCUGGAAGACCUGGAGGAGCAUGUGCCAGGGCAGACAGUCUCUGAGGAAGCCACAGGGGUUCACAUGAUGCAGGUGGACCCAGCCACGCUGGCAAAGAGUGACCUGGAAGACCUGGAGGAGCAUGUGCCAGAGCAGACAGUCUCUGAGGAAGCCACAGGGGUUCACAUGAUGCAGGUGGACCCAGCCACACUGGCAAAGCAAUUGGAAGACUCCACCAUUACAGGCAGCCACCAGCAGAUGUCAGCAAGUCCUUCCUCUGCACCUGCAGAAGAAGCAACAGAAAAGACCAAAGUGGAAGAGGAAGUGAAAACCAGAAAGCCCAAGAAGAAAACCAGGAAGCCCAGCAAGAAAAGCCGGUGGAAUGUCCUGAAAUGUUGGGACAUUUUUAAUAUAUUUUAGAGACCUCUGAAGAUUCCUCGACCACCAGGAAGGGCCCCGACGUGGGGAUGUCAACAUGGCUCAGACUUGAUGUGGAUCGUGAUCAUUUCGGGAAAUGUGUUACUCCAAAAACUUUUAUAAUCUUUGCUUAAUUUGUUUUUAAAUACUUUCCUGGCUGGGCGUGGUGGCUUAUGCCUGUAAUCCCAGCACUUUGGGAGGCCGAGGCGGGUGGAUCACCUGAGGUCAGGAGUUCAAGACCAGCCUGGCCAACAAGGUGAAACCCCGUCUCUACUAAAAAUACAAAAAUUAGCUAGGCGUGGUGGCGCACUCUUGUAGUCCCAGCUAUUUGGGAGGCUGAGGCAGGAGAAUCACUUGAACUCAGGAGGCGGAGGUUGCGGUGAGCCGAGAUCAUGCCACUGCACCCCAGCACCUGGCUACAGAGUGAGACUUUGUCUCAAAAAAAAAAAAAAAAGAACAAAAAAAUUCUGACUUUAACCUCUGUUUUUCAGAGGGCACAAAUUGUUCUUGUAUUGUUUCCAUUUUACAUUUUUUUCUUGAAGUUAUUUUCCAAUUGUUUUCAUUCUUUCUGAAGUUUUGUUUACUCGGUUUUAAGUUUUUGUAAUUUUGAUAGACUUCUUUUGUGCUUUCAUUUUCUUAAUGACUUUUACCUCAUUUUUAAAACAAAUCCAUAGUAUGGAUGAUAUUGAUGAUGAAAUGUCUUACGAUGAUCAUUUAGAGGUUUAUUUCGAACAACUGGCAAUUCCAGGAAUGAUGGAAUAAAGCAUACGAAGUAGAAGGACUGGAACCUCCAGAAAAAGUACUUUAAGUUACCUACAGGUGAUCCUAGUCAGGUAUGAAUUGAUAAGAAAUGCCUGCACCUUCCCUCCUUCCUAUCUUUCCCUUGCCUACAGAAAAUUAAAAGGCAAAACAAUGGACAUCUACAUAUUCUUCAUUCAGAUCAACCAGUGGCUAGCAUUUGCCACCUUUUGCAGUUUCUUUCUCUUUCCAUAAGUACUUUCUUCUCUGAAUCAUUUGAAAGCAAAUGAAAACAGUAGCCUAAAGUGUCAGUUUCAACCCGAAAAUAACAGCUCUGAUUUCUCAUGGCUCACACUCGUCUGAAAUGACUCGGGUAGAGGCUGAGGAAGGCUGUGUUGUUUGUCUACCUGGGACUACACCUACUGAAAGAAGUUCUCAAGUUCUGAUUGAGUUCUAAAAUUCUUUUGAAGAUUGGAAUUCUUCAUAUGUAAAAAGAGAAGAGAAAGACAUUCUUGAUUUUGGUGACUAGAGUUGUAGAUGCUGGAAGCUUUGCCACUAACAUUGAUGAACCAGAUGCAUGUCACCAGCCCAUCACGGUGAUUCUUAAUGCCGGCACCAUGGGCCGGCACUGCCACGUUUUCCAAGGAACCUGCCAGAGCUCCUGCGGAAGCUGCUCCUCGGGCGAUGGAGUCCCUUUGCUGCUAGGCCCUUCUUCAGUCACCACAGGAUGCCUGCCAUUCAUGAACAGGAAGGAGAGGACGGGCUUUGAAUAAAAAACAGGAUCCAGGAAAUAUUUGUGAGGCCAUUUGGACUUCAGUGUGAAAUGGUGUUAAAAGAUGAAGUCAUUUAUUCAAGAAGUAAACCUCUGCCACCUGGACUGUGCUCAGACAUUUCAUUGAUUUUGUUUAAUAAACAUUUUCUGGCUUUGGGAGGUGUCUCUCUUGGUAGAGCACAGUGUCAAAGAUGGACAAGAUGGACACAUAGUCCAUUAUUUGGUAUUGUUUGUGUAUGGGAGCGGACCACAAAUUAAUGUUUGGAGAACAAUUUUGUCAUAACACACUGUUGAGGCUCAGUUGUACAGAACUGGAAAAGUCUUUCAGCUUGGCACAUGUCCUGAUUCAGCCUUUGUUUAACAUACAUUCCAAUCCGGAUUCUAUCUUCACUGGCUACAAAGACCACCUGAUACGUGCACCACGACACAGGAGCUGCUGGAGAGGGGGUAGUGUUAUCACCUCAAACCCACAGCCAUAUUUUUCAAAAGCCAGCUUAGAGAGAGGUGUACUGAUAGCUGCAUAGAGAACAUGCAGUCCAUCCAUUCUUCCCAGUGAUGUACAUUUCUCAAUCAGUAACCACGUGGUAUACCAGCCUUGAGUGUCACAUCUCCCAACCAUACCAAAUGGAUCACCUAACUGGAGGUGGGGGGGGCCCCUCAGAAAUGAGAUUUCGUAUUUACUGUAAAAUUGCCUUAUUUUUUCUUUUGAGGUGGAGUCUCACUCUGUUGCCUGGGCUGGAGUGCAAUGGUGUGAUCACUGCUCACUGCAACCUCCGCCUCCUGGGUUCAAGCAGUUCUCCUGCCUCAGCCUCCCAAGUAGCUGCAAUUACAGGCGCAUGCCACCACUCCCAGCAAAUUUUUAUAUUUUUAGUGGAGACAGGGUUUCACCAUGUUGGCCAGGCUGGUCUCAAACUCCUGACCUCAGGUGAUCUGCCCACCUUGGCCUCCCAAAGUUCUGGGAUUAAAGGUACGAGCCACCGCAACUGGCUGAGAAUCUUUUUAUUUGCUGAUUUGUCUCUUGUGUAUUUUCUUUGUUCAGAUGUCUCUUCAGAUCUUUUUCUCACUUUUAAAUUGUUUUUUUAAUUGUUAAGAAUUUUCUGUCUAGUUUAGAUAUAAGCCCUUUAUCAGACAUGUGUUUUGCAAAUAUUUUCUCCUAGUCUGUGGCUUGUAUUCUGUCUCUUAACAGUCAUUUUAUUUUUACUUUUGAAACUAAAGAAGAAGAAUGGUCAGCUUUCCGUUAUUCUUGUAACAGUAAUGGCAGAACCAAGUCUGCUAAUGCUACAUUGAGCAAAGAAAGUCACCUGGUCAAGUCCAACAUUAAUGAAAUGGGGUAGUACAUGCAGGCGGCGUUGGGGUUGGGGAGGGAACAAAUGCUUCUUGAGAGUAAUAUAAUCUGCCAUACCAUCCAGGAACCUACAAUGGCUAUCUAUUACCUUAUUCUCUGGUUUGUUUAAUGUUCAAAUCUUUCCUAAAGAUCCUUCAACUUUUCUGGAAGAAUCUAAUCUGAUAACACCAUCAAAAACACAUUACUUCUUUUGGCAUAAUUUAAAUUGUAAGACAUCAUUCACAUUUAUCAAUGUUACAUAUAUAAGAACUCACCCACCAUAUUCCUCCUUGAGGAAUUACAGCAUGUAAUUCUAUAACCAUUUUUAUAAUCGUCUAACAAUUUUAUAAUGGAUUGGCUGCUAUCAAUUUUUUAAAAGUCAUGGCUUCUCCAGUCAUUUCUUGCUUAUCAAAAUUAUUUCAUGAGAUGGGUCUAUCCUUGUAUAUUUGAAAAUGAGGUUUGCUUCCUUCUACUUAAAAAACAACUUGAACAUACCUGUUUGGAUCACAUGGUCUUGUCCUGAUAACUUGGAAGAGGUUGCUUCAGCAUUAUUCUUAUUGUUGUGGUGGUUAUUAUUAACAUUGUUUCAUAUUCCGUUUAAAAAAUUAAAAUUUUACACAAGACCAAUGUCUUCUUUUCAAUUCCAGUACAGUCUUCAGAAGUAACUAAUGCUAUUGGCUUUGUGCAUUAUAAUUUCAGACCAUUGUAUAUGUCUUUAGUUAUAUGUACAGUAUACACACAUAUGUGUCAUAUUAUUCCAUUUUUUCUAGCAUUAAACAUUGCUAUGGAAAACUCUCAGAAAAAUA